GGGGAAAGCAGCCAGGGAGGUCGGGAGAUGGACGGAAACUGCUGGGGAUGUGAGAAGCCUGGGGCACUAACUGGAGUUGUUAUUGACUUGCGCUAGGAAGAAGAACCACUAUAGUGUUAACUGUAAUGGGCAGAAUGGCCCUUUAGUCACCCUUCCUGUGGCCUAACACUUGGACACUGUCACUUAAGAGGCCCCUCACAUCUACGCAGGAGAUGUAUGUGAGGUAGAGAGUGGGAAUCCUCAAUGAUGAGAAACCACCACCCGUCCCCCAAACUGGAGGCCACUGCUAAUUCUUUCAUUCUAUGCAUAAGACAACUGUGUGUACUGUAAUUUUACAGAUGAUGUCAAUGUAAAAUAGCAUGACUCUGGUUUUGGAUCUCAACUUUUUUCUAUGCAUAAUUAAGUGUAUUUAAAAUGAUUUAAAAUAAAUUAUGAGUCAUACCUCAGCCUUUCUUAACCAGUGAGAUGAAAUGUGAUGUGUCAAAAUUGAGUUAAAUCCAUAUUCUCUGUGGAUGUGCUUUUGACUUGCACAUAAGGAAAAGCAGGCAGGCAAAAGUGAGGCAGUUUCACACACUGUAUUGACAUUCAACAACGAGAAGGUCAGAGUAGGGAGUUGAUGUCAAUAUGUUCAUCCUGUACCGCAAUAAAGCUGUCCCGGCAACUGCAAUCCCAGCUGCCAUUUCCCCUCCUUUGGGUGAGAAAUGAGCCAUUCAGACCCUCAGCUCUUUAGCUAUGAAAACACCAUGCUUUAAGAAAGAUUUGGUUUUCAAUAUCAAUAUAAUCUAGGUUUCAGGCUUGGAAGAUAAAAUUUCCACACCAGAUAGGGCUUUAUUUGACAAAAACAGUAAGAGAUGACAGCUGAGAUUUCUGCCACAUGAAAAUUACCGAAUAAUUGCAUGGCAGGUGUCAUCAUUCUGAAUAUCAUAAAGUGAGUUUAGCACUCCAUUUUGCUUUCCAGUAUUUUACUGGGGAUGCUUUUCUUGGGGUUAUCAAGCAGUUUUAAAUGUUGGGAAAAUGUAAAAAGAGAGAGUAGACAUAAACAACAAUGGAAAAGGUAACACUUCACUAUAACAUUGCACUAUGUAUGUUCCAUUUUCCCUCAGGGAAACUACCGUAGAAUGGGCAAAAUCCUUCAGAAACGGGAGCCCACAAUGACCUCAACUCCUGCAGGCCUACAUGUUUUUUUAUCUCUGCCAGACCCACUGUCAAUUUUUUUUUUUUUUUUUUUUUGAGACGGAGUCUCGCUCUGUCGCCCAGGCUGGAGUGCAGUGGCGCGAUCUCGGCUCACUGCAAGCUCCGCCUCCCGGGUUCACGCCAUUCUCCUGCCUCAGCCUCCCGAGUAGCUGGGACUACAGGCGCCCGCUACCACGCCCGGCUAAUUUUUUAUAUCACUGUCAAUUUUUUAAAAGUCAGCUUGGAAAAAAUGAGAGAAUUUAAAAAAUUAACAACUAUUUCACAGUUGGUUCCUAUCUCUACUCAGUAUUACCCAAUUUAAAUUUUAUGUUGGUUUUCCAUCCAUUCCCCAGGCGCUUUCACAGAGCGGCCUGCCAGAGGCCAUUAGCACACACCCCUCACAAAUGGAGAAGCAGCGGCAUUCAGAUUCACCAGGAGCUGGACUGGCAUUUGCACUCACUCAGUUCACCUGGUGAUUGGCAAGCUUCUCUACUCUGAGUCGUGGUCACUUCCCUUCAGAAUAGAAUGUGGGGAACAACCUGAAGGGAUCGUGAUAAAAAAAGAUUGUCUUUGAUGUUGGAUGGGAUAUGCAAAUACGAAUGAGAAUAGGGUGCCUUAGUACUGUCAGAGUGUGCUGUGUUUUAUUUGGGAAAUGAGACAAAAUCUUCCCAUGAUCAGCCAUUCCAUGUGACAUCCCAACCCACACUCUGCUACUGACAUUUUAUCUCCCACUGAACAGCCUGGCUGUUGUAACAUUUUCAGGAUUCUUAAUUUAUGUCUUGCAGGAUCUAAAAUCAGAUGGCAGGAACUUUAAGAAAAUAACCAGUGUUGACAGGCACCUUAUAAAAGAAGCUGGUACACCUUAGUGCUGCUAAAAGUUAGAGAAUAUUCUUUCGUUUCUUCUUCCAAAAUAUGUCCAGAAGUCAGUGGGAUGGAGACAGUAGCUGUCCCAAAUCAUUUAAUUUCUCUUUUCAAUCUAAACUCUAUGAAAGGCUUUUUCUUUCACUCAAUAUUUGCUAGCGCCUGGGACUCAAGAAGGCUAAUGUCAAUGGAUCAUUUUCUUUUGAGGUAGUCGAACUUUUUGUCGUAGAAAAAUCUUCCUGAAUCUAUUCAGUAUCAAAACAUGGGGUGGGCCUGGCACGGUGGCUCAUGCCUGUAAUCCCAGCAUUUUGGGAGUCUUGAGUUUGGCAGAUCACUUGAGCCCAGGAGUUUGAGACUAGCCUGGGAAACAUGGUGAAACCCCAUCUCUACUAAAAAUACAAAAAAUUAGCCAGGCGUGGUGGCGCGCAUCUGUGGUUCCAGCUACCCGGGAGACUGAGGUAGGAGAAUCACCUCAGCCUGGGAAGUCAAGGCUGCAAUGAGCCGAGAUCACACCACUGUACUCCAGCCUGGGACAGAGUGAGACCCUGUUUCAAAAAGAAUUUAAAAAAAAAAAAAAAAAAAAGGAAAUCACUAGUCCCAAACCACUUAUCCUUGGAGAAAUAUGGACAUAAACCCAAAUUGCAUGUUCUUUCCAUUAUAUCACAGUGUCUCUUUGUAAAAGUGGCAACUUUGGGCUGGCUUACAUGAAUUCGCUGAAACCUUUACAACAUAUUGGCGGUGCUGAAUACUUGGGGCUCUUGAACGUAAGCCUGCAACCAGGAUGCUGGUGUACACCCUCACCCUGGAAUGCUCAGCCUUGAUCCUCCUCUUUUCAGAAUGGCUUCAUAUCUAUUUAUUUGUAACAUAGUGCUUAACAGUAGGAAGUCUUGAGCCAAAUGCCUAGCUCUGCCACUUAUCCCUGACCUGAGCAAGUUACUUAGCUUCUCCAGGCGUCAUUUUCCUGUAUUCUAAAAUGGAGAUGAUAAUAGCAUUUACCUUAUAGGAUUGUUGUGAAGAUUAAAUGAGUUUAGGGCAAUGCUAUAUAUAGGUUAGUAUCAUCCAUCAAUUUGCAACAUGAUUUCAUAAGUGCAUCUAGAAUAUGCUUGUGUAAACCUAUGGUUAGAUGAUGAAGCUAAGAAAAGCCUGAGUCCAUCCCUGGAGAGUAAGAAACUAGUAUACUCCUUUUACACAGUACCUUGCACACAGCACAGGCUUAACAGACAUAUUUAAAUUGAACUGAAGCGAAUACUACCAGAACUGAAAGUGGUAGUUCCAGAUCUUUCAGGCUCAAGGUCCAGAUUUUACAAGUGUUUCUGAUCACCCUCCCCCUACCUCAUUUAUCGCAAAGAGCAGAGGCCAGGAAAAGGAUGAAUAAUCAAUGACCUUAAAACUCAGGUGAGAAUAAAAACCAGUUCUGAGAAACCGUGUGACAUUUACAUCCUGGUACCUGAGCUUUAGAUCACUCUGCAUGUGUAUUUCCUCUGCACAAAGCCCAGGAGGCUACUUUUAUAUUAUUGGGGCAAAUCUCCCAACAGCCCUGGGUACUAAACAGCCUUCAGCAGGUGCUUCCAAAUUUUCUUAUUUGCUUCAACUCCCAGGUUGCCAGGGGAAGCUUGGCCGACAAGUCUAUACUCCUGGGCAGACUGAGCAACAGCAGGUGGUGGCUUCUGGAUAAGAGGUGCUCUAGGUCGGAAGGAAAUAAAUGAGACUACGAUCAGUUAAAGUUCGGUAAAGCAAGAGACGCCUUCAACCCGACGACCAGACGGUGGCUCCGCAGCACAGACUCUCUCGGAUGGUGGAAUUCCCAACCGGCUUCGAUGUAGCCCCGCCCCUACCCAGACCACGCCCACCAAUCACCGCCCUCUCCCCCCCAGGCCCCGCCUGGAGCCCGCCCCUCCUAAAGCAUGCUCCACCUGACUCCGACACUGCCGGGCUUAGUCCGCCGGGCUUAGUCCGUGGAGCGCUUGCGCAUUUCUUGAGUUGUCGUGGCACUGCCCAAAUCUGAAUGGGGGAAAGAGGGAACUUCAUAUUUCCUACAGACUCCGCCACAGCGACUUUGCGUGCUCUCUUAGAGCUGGUUUUGCCUUUCGUGGUCCUGAGAACCCUGGCUUUUGGUUCCCCAAUGCGGCUUAAGUGUGCAGGUUUUAAGUUAGGCGAUCUUCGGGCAGCCCUAGUCCCAGCACCGGGUCCUUGCGCUGAGUCUCGGGACCACAGCCGGGGAGGCGGGGUCCUUCUCUGGGGCGGUCGCGUUGGCAGCGGAUGCGGGAAGCCGGACUCUGGGCGUCAUGUACUACAAGUUUAGUGGCUUCACGCAGAAGUUGGCAGGAGCAUGGGCUUCGGAGGCCUAUAGCCCGCAGGGAUUAAAGCCUGUGGUUUCCACAGAAGCACCACCUAUCAUAUUUGCCACACCAACUAAACUGACCUCCGAUUCCACAGUGUAUGAUUAUGCUGGGAAAAACAAAGUUCCAGAGCUACAAAAGUUUUUCCAGAAAGCUGAUGGUGUGCCCGUCUACCUGAAACGAGGCCUGCCUGACCAAAUGCUUUACCGGACCACCAUGGCGCUGACUGUGGGAGGGACCAUCUACUGCCUGAUCGCCCUCUACAUGGCUUCGCAGCCCAAAAACAAAUGAGUUAGGCUGCAGAGGACUGGUUUGUUUUUUGGCAUAAACCCUUUGAAGUUCCUUUUUCAUUGUUAAAUUAAAAUUUUUUUUUUUACUUGGAUGGCUUAACAUUUUUGCAAGAAAAAUAGGAAGAUAUGAAGAUGAUGUUUUGGUUUGUUUAUGAAAUGCAUAUGGCUUGUCAGAGCUCAUUCGACAGUUAAAGCCAUUGUUUAAAGAAAUGGUGCUUUGCUCUGUGUUUGUGCUCCUGAUUUCCCUGGAGGUUCUGGAUGAAGGCUGAACACAGGCUUGUUAAUGUCAGUCUGUGCUGAGGACCUCAGGGACUUGAGGUUGCAUUUUUGAGCAUGGGGUGCAGGAGCCUUUCUGGAUUUGGAUGUGGCUAUGGAAAGAACACAGAAGCCAAGGUCAUGUGCAUGAAAUGAGGAGUUUGAGUUAGUCACCUCGGGGAUUUUUUCCAUUUUGCAGUAAAAUGUUAAAUUAAUGUAGCCUGCCUCUAUUUGUUGGGCAGGUAAUUUCAAAGGGUUAUUUGCCUCAUCUCCUAUCUUUAGUGAAAUCUUAUGUGUAAUUAUUCCACCGUGGGAACAGAGAAUACCUGUUUAGUGUUGCACUUUAGACUGGUGUCUGUUUUGUUAAUGCAGCUGUGCCACAAAUUCUCCUUUAUCUUUUAAAAAUGUUAUAGCUUUAAAUUUUGAUUUAUUUUGACUGUGGAAUAAAUACAUGAAUGAAAAAUUUUAAGUUUGAAGUUCUUUGAAUGACCUUUCAGAGUAAUUUCAGAACACCAGCAGCAUCUUAAACCUGAGUCUAAUUUCUUUCUUGUUAAUUAGGCACCAGAUAAUCUUUAUAAAAUGGUUCUUAAAAGUCUAGUAAUAGGAGUCUUAAUGGCAUAUUGAUGAUUACCACAUGGUUUUUUAUAAAAACCUGCCUGCCCCUUAGUGAAAGGUACCUGUAACUCACAGUUCAUUUAGACACUAAUUUCCUUUGCUGUCAUGAUUGGUAGACUUCACUUACCCUAUAUUAAUUUUGAAAAAAGGUGGAAUUUUAUUAUAUAUGAAGGAAUAGUUUGUAUCUUACCAUAGCACAGAACAGUGACCUCUUGCUCAGGAUAAGAUGUGGUGAUUUGAAAAUACUCAAUAGUAGCCUUGCAGUGAUAUCUCUCUCUCUCUCUCUCUGCAAAUCUAAAUUUUAUUCUCUGGUAUUUCCUCCAAGUUUUUAUUUUGAAAAUUUUCAGACUACAGAAGGACUAAGCAUAGUACAAUAUACACCUGUAUAUCCUUCACUUAGAUCACCAGUUAUCAAUAUAUUGGCACCUUUGCUUUUUCUUGUUCUCUCACACAGGCACACACAAUGCAUAUAUGCACACACACAUAGAUCUGUUUUUUGUUGAGUCAUUUAAGAUUGUUAGGGAAUUAUGAUAAAUCAGCCAUAGUACUUUAGCAGGUAUCUUCUGAGUAAGGACAUGUGUUCCUUUAUAACCAUAAUGCAGUUGUCAGACUCAAUAAAGUUAACAUUUAUAACAAUACUACCAUCUAAUACAUAGUUUACUUUCAGAUUUCCCCAGGUGUUCUAAUAAUGAGUUCUUCAUAGUUGUGUUUUUAAAAAAUAACAGCUUUAUUGGGAUAUAAUUUACAUACUGUACAGUUCACCUCAAGUGUACAAUUCAUUGGUUUUUACUGUAUUUGGAGUUGUACAGCCACCAUGAGAAUCAAUUUUAGAACACUUAUAUCACCCUAAAAAGAAACCCCAUACCCAUUAGCAAUCACUUGCCUUCCCUCCCACCAUCCCAACUCCCACCUCCUAGCCCAAAGCAAGCACUCAUCUACUUUCAGUCUCUAUGGAUUUGUCUUUCCUGGACAUUUCAUAUAAAUAUAAUCAUAUGAUGUGUGAUGUACGUGA